GCCUUCCUCCUCCUCCUCUCGCCGCUACCGCCGUCGCCGCCGCCGCAGCCGCCGCCAGUCCGCGCGGCCUCGGGUGGCCGGAGCUCAGCCUGCGCGCGCCGCGCCCUGUGUCUCCGGGUGGGGCAGAAGACUCGCCCCUUGAACCUCCCGCGGGGACUCUCCGUGGUGUGGCGGCCCUGGGGCUCUUUCUUAAUAGCCCCGGACUGAGUCCCCUCCAGUCGAGGACCCUCUCCUAGUCCACUGACGAGCGGUGGACACCUGCCGCUGUAUCUCCCCCAAACCGAGUCCUUGCCCUGCUGCCUCCUCAUACCCACACGGCGGCAGAGACCUUCACCAUAGCGUUCGCUCAACUCCAGAACCUUCCGACCUCCGCUAGUUCCUGCGGGCCUUUGCCCGCUUCCCGGUGCACCCUCCCCGGGAGACACCUCAGACCCCCGACAGCCUGGGCAGGCUCGGUGCCUGCGGGUGCGUUCCUGAUCACCCCUCCCCUCUUCCCUCCCCCUCAUCCUCCAUUCCCUUGUUUUCACCCUCUGUCCUCUGCCCGUCACUCCCCUUGUCACCUCUUGGAGCCCCCUCCUAACCAGCGGCCAGUGGGUUUCCCAUACCCCAGGAUGUGAGCCUCUUUAACCUGUAAUGCUGUGGCUAGCCCUUGGCCCCUUUCCUGCCAUGGAGAACCAGGUGCUGGUAAUUCGCAUCAAGAUCCCAAAUAGUGGCGCGGUGGACUGGACAGUGCACUCCGGGCCGCAGUUACUCUUCAGGGAUGUGCUGGAUGUGAUAGGCCAGGUUCUGCCUGAAGCAACAACUACAGCAUUUGAAUAUGAAGAUGAAGAUGGUGAUCGAAUUACAGUGAGAAGUGAUGAGGAAAUGAAGGCAAUGCUGUCAUAUUAUUAUUCCACAGUAAUGGAACAGCAAGUAAAUGGACAGUUAAUAGAGCCUCUGCAGAUAUUUCCAAGAGCCUGCAAGCCUCCUGGGGAACGGAACAUACAUGGCCUGAAGGUGAAUACUCGGGCCGGACCCUCUCAACACAGCAGCCCAGCAGUCUCAGAUUCACUUCCAAGCAAUAGCUUAAAGAAGUCUUCUGCUGAACUGAAAAAAAUACUAGCCAAUGGCCAGAUGAAUGAACAAGACAUACGAUAUCGGGACACUCUUGGUCAUGGCAACGGAGGCACAGUCUACAAAGCAUAUCAUGUCCCGAGUGGGAAAAUAUUAGCUGUAAAGGUCAUACUACUAGAUAUUACACUGGAACUUCAGAAGCAAAUUAUGUCUGAAUUGGAAAUUCUUUAUAAGUGCGAUUCAUCAUAUAUCAUUGGAUUUUAUGGAGCAUUUUUUGUAGAAAACAGGAUUUCAAUAUGUACAGAAUUCAUGGAUGGGGGAUCUUUGGAUGUAUAUAGGAAAAUGCCAGAACAUGUCCUUGGAAGAAUUGCAGUAGCAGUUGUUAAAGGCCUUACUUAUUUGUGGAGUUUAAAGAUUUUACAUAGAGCAAACAAAGACCUGUGCACCUGAAAAGGGUGAGUGAAUUUUACUGUGUAUAAAUUAUGCCUCAGUAAACCAAAUUUUAAAAUUAAAAAGUAAACCAGAUUUACAGAGAAAAGCUCUUCUUACAUCUUAGCAGUGCAGUAGACACUCUAGAAAGAAGUUUUCCCUGCCAAAAGGACAAACCAUUCUUUCAAAGGGUCUUGGUGAUUCUGUUAUUGUUUCUGUAUCUUCAUGGUUCCUGACAAAUCCUACCUAGGUUUGAUCUAGUAACUCAGUAGCUUAAAAAACAGCCAGCCAACCCCCCCACCCCAAGAAAAAAAACCAACCCUUGUGAUUUAAAGGAUAUCUACAAUGCCAGAAAGAGAGAGACAGGGUCAGGGAAGGAAGGAUAGUGGGAAGAGAAACAGAAACUUAGAAGUUGCUGUUAUCAUUGGCACAAUUUGAAACAUCUGGAAAUUGGACAGUUCUUUCUGUAGUUAAGCCGAUUUUUUUCCCCAGAGAUAUUACCAAGAACUGCGUAUCUGCAGAGCUGACUUAACCUGUUGGACAAUUUUAAAAGCUCAGUUUCUAAGAAGGAAUAAGGCUUUAUCUGACAUUCCCAAUUCAGUCCUACUGACUGACUGCCUCACUGGGUGACCCCAGAAAGGCAGAUCACUCCUGUUCUCUUUGCCUCUGUUCCCUCAUGUAUACUAUGAAAGAGUAGCUGGAUGAUCACUCAGAUUUCUUCAAGAGCUAAGGUUCUGGGUUCUGUGAUUUCCUGACUGAAGGAAGUGUGACCUGUUGAUAAGGUGGGGAACAAAGAAAAUCAGAGAGACAUAAAAGAAAAGAAAGAGAAAAGGGAGGGGAGAAUUUCCAAGAGUAGAUUUUGUGAUGAAAAUAAUAACAAUAAUGACUAUUAAGCAUGUACUCUGUACCAGGCACUGUUCUAGGUGCUUAAUGUAUAUAAAUUAUUUAAGGUAUUCCUUCAAAGUGGGAAAUUCUAGGAAAUAUGAAAUGUUUUAAAACUGAAGAUAAGAGACUAAAGUAUAAAACAAAUAAUUGAAAAUUAAAGCUGUGUGCCUUAGCUAAGAAAAUGUUGCUUUCUAAACCAGACUCAUGUUAUCAAAUCAAAAGGCAUCUUUAAGGGAAACUGUUUUUAAAGUAUCAGGGACACUGAAAAUGAAGUAUUAUAAUUAAUAAGGAAUUAUAAUAAGGACAUGUAAAGUCACAACUUGGAUGGAAAGCAAGAACACGUUUUUUUUUCUUUUAUUUUUAUUAUCAUUAUACUUUAAGUUUUAGGGUACGUGUGCACAAUGUGCAGGUUAGUUGCAUAUGUAUACAUGUGCCAUGCUGGUGUGCUGCACCCAUUAACUCGUCAUUUAGCAUUAGGUAUAUCUCCUAAUGCUAUCCCUCCCCCCUCCCCCCACCCCACAACAGUCCCCAGAGUGUGAUGUUCCCCUUCCUGUGUCCAUGUGUUCUCAUUGUUCAGUUCCCACCUAUGAGUGAAAACAUGUGGUGUUUGGUUUUUUGUCCUCAUGAUAGUUUACUGAGAAUGAUGAUUUCCAGUUUCAUCCAUGUCCCUACAAAGGACAUGAACUCAUCAUUUUGUAUGGCUGCAUAGUAUUCCAUGGUAUAUAUGUGCCACAUUUUCUUAAUCCAGUCUGUCAUUGUUGGACAUUUGGGUUGGUUCCAAGUCUUUGCUAUUGUGAAUAGUGCUGCAAUAAACAUAUGUGUGCAUGUGUCUUUAUAGCAGCAUGAUUUAUAGUCCUUUGGGUAUAUACCCAGUAAUGGGAUGGCUGGGUCAAAUGGUAUUUCUAGUUCUAGAUCCCUGAGGAAUCGCCACACUGACUUCCACAAUGGUUGAACUAGUUUACAGUCCCACCAACAGUGUAAAAGUGUUCCUAUUUCUCUACAUCCUCUCCAGCACCUGUUGUUUCCUGACUUUUUAAUGAUCGCCAUUCUAACUGGUGUGAGAUGGUAUCUCAUUGUGGUUUUGAUUUGCAUUUCUCUGAUGGCCAGUGAUGAUGAGCAUUUUUUCAUGUUUUUUGGCUGCAUAAAUGUCUUCUUUUGAGAAGUGUCUGUUCAUGUCCUUCGCCCACUUUUUGAUGGGGUUGUUUGUUUUUUUCUUGUAAAUUUGUUUGAGUUCAUUGUAGAUUCUGGAUAUUAGCCCUUUGUCAGAUGAGUAGGUUGUGAAAAUUUUCUCACAUUUUGUAGGUUGCCUGUUCACUCUGAUGGUAGUUUCUUUUGCUGUGCAGAAGCUCUUUAGUUUAAUUAGAUCCCAUUUGUCAAUUUUGGCUUUUGUUGCCAUUGCUUUUGGUGUUUUAGACAUGAAGUCCUUGCCCAUGCCUAUGUCCUGAAUGGUAAUGCCUAGGUUUUCUUCUAGGGUUUUUAUGGUUUUAAGUCUAACGUUUAAGUCUUUAAUCCAUCUUGAAUUAAUUUUUGUAUAAGGUGUAAGGAAGGGAUCCAGUUUCAGUUUUCUACAUAUGGCUAGCCAGUUUUCCCAGCACCAUUUAUUAAAUAGGGAAUCCUUUCCCUAUUGCUUGUUUUUGUCAGGUUUGUCAAAGAUCAGAUAGUUGUAGAUAUGCGGUGUUAUUUCUGAGGGCUCUGUUCUGUUCCAUUGAUCUAUAUCUCUGUUUUGGUACCAGUACCAUGCUGUUUUGUUUACUGUAGCCUUGUAGUAUAGUUUGAAGUCAGGUAGCAUGAUUCCUCCAGCUUUGUUCUUUUGGCUUAGGAUUGACUUGGCAAUGCGGUCUCUUUUUUGGUUCCAUAUGAACUUUAAAGUAGUUUUUUCCAAUUCUGGAACACUUUUUUUUUUAAUCUUUUUGUUGUGAAACAAUGGUAGAUCCACCGGAAGUUGCAAAAAAAUGCACAAGACAGUCCCAUCUAAGGGCAUCCUUUUUAAGGAAGGAAUUUUGAAGAAAAUGGGAAGGUGAGAGGGUAACAGUUCAAAAUAGUGUAGGCAGGUAAAUGUUAUAUAUUUGAUAUUGUCCUUUAAGUGAAAUCAGUAUAAAUUUUAAGAUUAAAAAUGUUAUAAGAAUAUUUGUAUUAUAUUCCAAAAUUAUUUUGUUAUAUUUAUUAAAUGGGAAAAGAGAAAUGGUUUGGUAGAGGUAAAACGUUUGAAUUCCUUAGGAAAGAAAUUUUGAUGUCAAGGUGGUAGUUAAAAUAGUAUGUUAGUGUGUGUAAAAGUUGGGAUUUGGGGCAAAAAUAAAUUAGGGAAUGAUUAUUUUCUGGAUAAAGUGAUUCUUAAACAAAAGAAUUCUUGGAAAGUAUUGCUAUCAAUAGAAAACUAACCUGAUUAAUUUUUAAUGAUUUAUUAAAAGAUAAUUUGCAUAAAGCUUUGUAACAAUCUGUUUUUUUGCAGAGAUCUACAUAGUUUGUGAUUAACUAUAUACAUUAUAGUGAAUUUUUAAAUAACCUAUGACAUAUUUUUGCUUUCUGGAGGAUCAGUUUUUGUUUGUUUGUUUAUUUUUUUGAAACAGAGUCUCACUCUGCCGCCCAGGCUGGAGUGCAGUGGCACAAUCUCGGCUCACUGCAACCUCCACCUCCCAGGUUCAAACGAUUCUCCUGCCCCAGCCUUCCAAGUAGCUGGGAGUACACACACGUGCCUCCAUGCCCGGCUAAUUUUUGUAUUUUUAGUAGAGACAGGGUUUCACCAUGUUAGCCAGGCUGGUCUCGAUCUCCUGACCUUGUGAUCCACCCGUCUCGGCCUCCCAAAGUGCUGAGAUUACAGGCAUGAGCCACCGUGCCCGGCCCCAAACACUUUUUUAAAAGAACUGGUUAGUGCUUGAGUAACCCAAGUAAAUUUAAAAGGAGUCAUUCCCAGUAGGUUUUAUGUUGCCAUGUGUAAUGAUGAGAGAGCUAGUAUGUGCGUUCUUCCUUCCCUGAGCUCUCAGGCUGUUUAAUCAGAUGGGUCUGGAAGGAGGCAUUUAUGUUAUACAAGUGCUAGUGUUGAGAGCACAGUUAACAUCCUAUCUCCUGUGUAAAAAUCAUUUCCAUAUUGUCCUUUAAAUAUAAUAAAUAUUAAUCACAUCCAGCGCUAUAGUAGAUUAUAACUUGUGAAUGUGUAUGUUUUUGAAAAGAAAAAAAAAGACUUAGCCCAUUAACAGGGUAAACAAACUCUGACUCUAGGUUGUUGGUUUUUCUCCAGCUCUGACACUAUCCACACAAAUGAACAUCUCGAGAAAUUAAGCCUCUUUCCCCAUAUUGGUCAUUCAUUCUAUUUACCUUGGGUGAUCACAGGGUAUUUCUGUAUUUGCAGUAUGUUGUGAUUUUCAAGAGAUCAGAAACGCUACAUGUCUUAAAAGUAUUCUUUUAAAAGAAUAUGUGCCUAGAAUAUAUAAAGAACUCUCAAAACUCAAUGGUAGAAAAACAAACAAUCCAAUUAGAAAAUGGGCAAAGACAUGAAGAGACAUUCCACUGAAGAGUAUACACAGAUGGCAAAUAAGCACAUGAAAAAGAUGUUCAAUAUCAUUAGGCUUUAGGGAAAUGCAAAUUAAAACCACCAUGAGAUAUUACUAUAUACCUAUCAGAAUGGCUAAAAUAAAAAAUAGUAACAAUAGCAAAUGAGGAUGCAGAAAAUUGGAUCACUAAUACAUUGCUGGUAGGAAUGUAAAAUGAUACAGCCCCACUGCUGACAUUUAAAAAAAAGAGAAAGAAAGCUAGACAUGCCACUACCGUAUGACCCAGCAAUUGCAUUCCUGGGCAUUUAUCCCAGAGAAAUGAAGACUUCUGUUCACACAAAAACCUGUACGCAAGUGUUUAUUGCAGCUCUAUUCAUCAUAGCCAAAAACUGGAAACAACUCAGAUGUCCUUCAACAGGUGAAUGGUUAAGCAAGCUGUGGGCAUUCAUACCAUGGAUUACUGCUCAGCAAUAGAAAGGAGCGAACUGUUGAUGCCCACAACCUAGAUGAACCUCCAGAUCAUUAUACUGAGUGAAAAAGCCAGUCACAAAGGUUACAUAGUGUAUGAUUCCAUUUGUAUAAUAUUCUUGAGAUGACAAAAUUAUAGAAAUGGAGAGAGCACAUUAGUGGUUACCAGGGGCUGAGAGGAUGGGAGACAGAGGGAAUGUUUACAAUGGAGCAAGAUGAGGAAUCCUCAUGGUGAUGGAAAUGUUCUCCAUCUUGACUAUCAGUGUCAAUACCCUGGUUGUGAUACUAUACUACAGUUUUAUAAGAUGUUACCAUUAGGGGAAACUGGGUGGAGUGUACACAGGAUGUCUCUGUAUUAUUUCUUACCAUUGUAAAUGUAAACUUUGAGAUAACUGUGUAAAUCUAUAGUUAUCUCAAAAUUAAAAGCUUAAUGUAAACAACAAAAAAAGAAUAUAUCAUCUUUCUGUAGUUACCUGUAUUCAGAAGGUCAGCUUAAUCAGAGAAGGUUGUCCUGGACUUAGUUUUUCUCUCUCCCAUGCUUCUGUGGUAGGAUUUGAUCAUAGGCAGAGUCAUCCCUUUUAGGAAAUCAGUAAGAGGGAAAUUACCCUCUUCCAUUCUGAAAAUGAGUAUCAAUGGAAGCCUUAGAGGAGAAAUAAGGAAAGACGUCGUGUGUCAUUCAAGGAACAAAUGCAAAUGGAAGAGGAUAGUUAUUUCCCCAGUCCCCACCUCUAAAAGCCUUCUGACUUGCAGGGGAUUGGGAUUUGAAGCAGACUGUGUGAUCGUUGUGUGUUUUGGCUCACCAGUCUCUAUAGUAUCCAUUAGGGUAAGCUUCUAUCCAACCACCCAGCAAGAUGCCCCCAGUGUGUGGAUGAGUGUUUGAUUCACCAAGCCCCGCAGUUAGCUCUGAUCAUUGCUUUGUCUCUGACACAAACCUGAAGUUUAGGAGCUUAUCAGAGGGAGAGAGAGAGCACCUGUAUGAUGAAUGACAGGGUCAUUUCUGUUGGUAGAGGAGUUUAUGGCAUUGAUUGUAUGCCAGUGGAUAUUUGUUGGAUGAAUACAUUGAAUCAUAAUUUUCUGAGGGCAGUGUUUUUCUCCUGGAACUUUUUAUAAUGUGGCUAAAUUGGAAGUCAUCUUUUGUUCCCCUUUCUCGUAUUAAAGUAAGAGAUUUAUCCUUGGGACAUUUUGCCAAGCAGAAUGGACAGACAGCUUUAGCAGUUGGAAGAGCUCUCCAUGUCUCUUCCUUUCUCUAAAGGCAUGGUUGAAGGUGAUCAGCACCAUGGAAAUCAAAUCUACUCUUUUGCUGGUGGAAGAUUAAGUUCCUUCUGGAUUGGGUACAAUCAUAAUGAUAACAAUAUUAAUCAUUUUCCUAAUAUCAUUUAUUGAGUACCUUGUAUGUGCUACAGUGUUAGCUCUCUUGUAUGUAUAAUUUUAUUUAAUUGUUAUAAUAACCUUGUGAGGAGGUAUCAUUGUAUCUCCAUUCUUAGGUGAAGCAAUCAAGGCUCAAGCAGCCUAAAAAACUUGCUUAGUUAUAGGAAAAGUCAUAGGAAAAAGUCAUAGGAAAGUGGUUGGUGGCCUAAUGGAAAAGCUCUAGUAUGAGGGUCAGACCCAGGUUUAAGUUCUGGUUCUUCCUCUUAAUUCAUCUUAGCUAUGUGACCUUGGGUCAGCUUCUUAACUUCUUUGAGGUCAUAGCAUUGUACCUGGCAUAUAACAGCUAUUAUUAUGUCAAAUAAUUAUUUCUCAAGAAAAGAAGCAAGAGGUUAAAUGAGAGGGAAUAGUUAGAACGUUCCUCACACUUUCCUGUUAACAUCUCCUUUUCUUAGAAAAUUAGCCUGUGAGUAUAAAGAACUUAAAACAUCUGGGCUAUUUUCUUUGUGAACUUCCCAAGAUCACCCAACUAUUCACUGCCAAAGCUGGGAUAAUCCAUCCUAUUAGUUCCAAUAAGAUUUAGCUCAUAAAUAUAAUGCAGUUUGUUAAGGCUUAAGAGCUUUACUAGUCGAAGCCUCUAGUUUUGUGUCCUUGGGCAAGUAAUUUCAUUAAUUUGAACCUCAAUUUCCUCCUCUGUAAAAUGGGGUUAAUAAUAGUACCUAUCUCAAGGGUUACAAUGAGAAUUAAAUGAGGUAAUGCAUAUGAUAAUAAUGCACUUAGCCCAGUUCCUGGUAUAUAUUAAGUGCCAAGUAAGUGUUAUCUACCAUAAUUUUUUGUUAUUUCUUUAAAACAAAUUACCAGGAUUAGUCUUCGGGACACACCGCUCCAAGUCAAGUCUGCUGUCUUACAUCUUAUUUAUGCAUAUAAUGUGGUAUUCCUUUGUUUUCUUUCCUUUUUCCCCAAAAAUGUUUUAUAGUCAAGAGGAGUCUUAACAGUCAGUGGUAUCUUAGACUUGGGGAAGUAGGUUGUGCAGGAACACAUUCCUCCAGACCUGGCUUUUCCUAAACACUGACCAGAAUAUGUACACAUCACAGGUAGGAAUCUAAGAUUCACCACUUUAGAAGGAAAUCUCUUUUACUUACUAUGAAAGGAUUAAGAGAGGGAGAAUUGAGAAGCUCAGGCCUUUUUGCCCUUGUUAUUAAUCUUGUAAGUGUCCCAGGUACCCUGCCUUUAUUGAAGAAGGAAAGGGCACGUUUGUUGCCUCCAUUCUGAACCGAAUCAUGAGACUCCAGGCAAUAACUGCCAUUGAGGAUGGCUAAUUAUGCUGUUUAAUUUUAUUUAAGGCCUUUGCAAGAAUAUUUGGAUGACCUACCCUUUCUUAUGUGAUGGAGUCAUUAGAAUAACUUUUAUAUUGCAAUGUGGUUUUCUCUUAAGUAUGUUCCCGUUGUGCACAGAUGAAUUUGUAAUGCAGAACGUCAGCAUAGUCUAUACUUAAUUGUACCUGCUGUUCUCAUUCAUUAGAAUGCAGUCCCCAAUAAAUAACUAGAUAGAUAUAUUGUUUUUUUUCUUUUCAUAAGACAAUUAAACAUAAUGAAAGAGCAUUGCUGAAGAUCCCAGGCACAGUGCUAGGAGAGGUUGCUAGGAGUGGAGACCGGCUAAUGUGCCCUCUGGCUCCUGGUAAACUGAGAGUGGCUUCCUGGUAUUCACACAGUGUAAUUGCUUUAUAGGGGGAAAAAGUUGAAGAGAAGUUUAUUUCUGCCUCCAUUGUCAUCCCACAACAGCCACAUGCCACAUUUAAAAAUGUUUCUGUAACAAUUGUACCAUGCCUGUUUCUAAGAGCAUUCAGUGAGACAUGUAAAAGUUCAGAGCAAAUUAAAUGUUUAAAUAUGAAACAAAGACCAAAAGGAAGUAGAAGUUGGAGAUACCAACAGCACCUGAUGUGAAUAGGUCACAACAAAAAGGGAAUCCUCAAUUGGUAUGGUUUUUCUUUUCUGGCAAAAGAAAGCAUAUAGCUGAUACAAAAAUCACAAUUUUCUUUAGAACUGAUCUUACCAGACACCGGGCACAGUGGCUCACGCCUGUAAUCCCAACACUUUGGGAAGCCGAGGCGGUAGGAUCAUGAGGUCAGUAGUUUGAGACCAGCCUGGCCAAUAUGGAGAAACCCCAUCUCUACUAAAAAUACAAAAAUUAGCGGGGCAUGGUGGUGAGCACCUGUAGUCCCAGCUACUCAGGAGGCUGAGGCAGGAGAAUUGCUUGCACCUGAGAGUCGGAGGUUGCAGUGAGGUGAGAUCGUGCCACUGCACUCCAGCCUGGCAACCGAGUGACACUGCAUCUCAAAAAAAAAAAAAAAAAAGAACUAAUCUUACAAGGAAAUUACCGUUUGGGUCCCUAUACAAAGCACAUUAAGUAACUCCAACUGUAGUUUUGUGAAGGAGCUUUUAUUUGUUUUGAACAGCCCCCUCGGCACCCAGCCAGAUCCUAGCCAAGGGUAACCUCCCACCCUGACCCCUGAUUGUGCUGGGGGCAGGGGCUGGGCAGUGGGCGGAGGAGCCCUUUUGUGAAGAUGUUGGGAAAGCACAUGCUCUUGAGGCUCUGGCCUUUAUUAGCAAGCUUCUGCUUGAUGCUGUUUAUGUGGAUUGUUUAAUGGCUAAUUGAUGCAGAAUGUGUAAAGAUACAGUUUCCUGCGUGAGGCAGUUAUGGGUGGCAACAUGGGUUGUCUCAACACGAUACCAAUUUCCACAGUCAAUUUGGCCAAUUCAGUGGGGGGAAAAAAUCAGUCCAGCCUGAAAAUCAGAGCAGCUACUUGCGGUUAUUGAGGCAACUAUGGUUGGUGGACCAAAUUUUUCAUGUUUGAAUCAGUUGUUUUUACAUUUUAUAGACAUAGCCUUACUCAUUUCUUGAAAUAAUCUUAAAUACACAAAAGUAACAUUUUAAAAUUAAUAUCUUUCUUUAAAUAUUUGUAAUUGCGGUUUAUCAGGCCUAGAGCAUAUCAGUUCUAAGAGGAAAUAACCAUUUUACCAUUGAUAUAUAGUAUAUGUAAUUAACUGAUCUUUCAUACUUUG